AUAAUACUAUUCCAAUGUCUUUGUGUGCUAAUUCUAACAUCUGUAUUAGUUCUGAGUCAUUUUAGAUUGGUUGAUUUUUCUUCAUACAAAGGACUAUAUUUUCCUGCUUAUUUGCACUUUUGUAGAAUUUUUAUUGUGUAUCUGUGGAUUUUACCAGUUUAGGUAGCGAAUAUUUUGAAUAUCUGUAAAUACUCUUAACCUUCCUUCUGGGGUGCAGUUAAGUUAACUUGAUUCUCUUGGGUCUUGCUUUUAGGUUUUGUUAGUUGGGGCAGAGUAUCAUUUAGUCUAGGGUUACUUUUGCCUUAAAACUGAGGCAAACUUUUCUCUCCAAAGUGUCCCACGAAUUAGGAGGUUUUCUAGUCUGACUAAUGGGAACAGGCCCCAUGUGAAUUUCAGGUACUGUUCCUUCUAAUCCUUCAGAGUGGUUCUUUCCCCAGAGUCAUGUCGUUUCCUCACAUUUUGCACUGGUUAAUGUUUUCUGGGAUACUUAAAGUAGAACCUUUGCAGAUUUCUGUGAUUCUUUCUCUUUGUAGCUUUUUCCUCGCUGCUGCUGUAAACUCUAAGCUGCCUUGGUCCCCUCAGACUCCCAACUCUUUUUCUCUCAGCUCAGGGAGUUGGAUGGGCUCUAUUUUGGUUCCUCCAGUGCUCCAUGGCCUGGACCCUCUAUCAAGGGAGUAAGCUGGGGCAAUCAUAGGGCUCACAUCAUAUGUAGCCCCUCUCUCAAGGAACAUGUUCUUCAAUGCCUGAAAUCUGCUGUCUUGAAAAACCAUUGUUUCAUAUAUUAUCCAGUUUGUUGUCAUUGUUUUGAGACAGGGUCUCACUCUGUCACCCAGGCUGGAGUGCAGUAAUGAGAUCAUGGCUCAAGUGAUCCUCCCACCUCAGCCUCCCAAGUAGCUUUUUUGUUGUUUCAGGCAGUGGGUUAAAUCCAGUUUCUUUUGUUCCAUCUUGGUUGGAAGCAGAAGUAUUAGGUAGACAUGUCCAUUGAAGGGUUUUCUUUUCUUCUCCAAUUUGGCAGCAUUUUUAGGAAAGUAUUUCUUUUUAUCUUGGUUUUUACUUUUUUAUUACUGACCUGUAUCUUUUAUCAUAAGAAUACAGUUGUCCUAAAUCUAUUUUUUCAAUUGUCUGAAUUUUCUUAAAUGAUUCAAGGCAGAACAAAUGAAGAAUGCUUUCUUUUGAGAAUUCCAAAGUUGUAUAGAUGGUGGGUAUACUUGUAUAAAUUUGGUUGAUUAUUACCUUUUAUGUUAUAUUGUGUAGAUUAUAAGGUAGAAUGGGCUAGGAUUGCUUUUUUUCCCUGCCAGUAAAAGUUCACAGAAUCCAGUAAAUGCCAAGUAUAUCCAAUAAAGAAACAAACACAAAUGAUAAGGAUGUUUUGAGUUGACAAGCUUUUCUGUACAGUUGUUAUUUAAGGGAUAGGGUAUUGAACAAUGAUUUCUCUAAGCAGCAGUUCCAUAUGCCAUGACUGUAUAAACUUAUACAUUAUAGCUAAAGGGAACUUGCAUUCUUUCCACUCCAUUAAAAAUGUACUGUCAUUUUCUUAACUUCACGUUAUGAGGCGUGGAUUUAACAAACUUUUUUGGAGGGUUUGGCAAACGGCAUUUGACCUAUAUUCCCUCAUUUUUUAAAUGGUAGUAUUUGCUAUGGCUUUGCUUUUGAUGACUGUUAGUCAACUGUUUCUCUCUUGAACAAAAUGGUGUGCUCUCACCAGCCUAUCACACAUCAGACUUAGAGCCAUGACAUUUGAAUUUAUUCAUUCCUAACUUGUUAUUUUAAGAAUAUCCUCAGAUAUUAUUGGGCAAUUACUAUCUUUCAGGCAAGUGCUAAGUUUCAAGCAUGUAUGGUGAAAAGACUUGAUCUUUGUUCUCAGCCAAGGAGCAUUUAGUGACAAAUAAUCAUUAUAACACAUUGUGAUAAAUUAUUUGCUGAGUUGUUCAUGUGUUUUACAAAUAUUUACUGAGAAUCUGCUAUGUGCCAGAUAUUAAUACAGGCUGUGGGUUUAUAGCAGUGAAUAAUUCCCUAGUCUCAUAGAGCUAACAUUUUAAUGAGGAGAAAAAUGAUGAUGUGGAGGGAGUGGGAGAGUGGAGAAAUGCUAGGAAGAUAAAUUAGAGUAAGAAAAUGGAGCUUGUCAGUGGAAGGGUGUUGCCUUUUUACAGUGGUCAAACUCUUGUUGUAAGGUGACAUUUGAGCCAAGACCUUAAAGAAAUUGAGAGGAUAAGUCACUCAAAUAUCUGGGGGAAAGUGUUCUAAACAGAGGCAGAUAUAAAAAUAAGAAAGGAUGAGUGUGCCUGCUGUGACUGAAGAGCCAGAAAGGGUCCAGAAUAGCCAGUAGAAUGAGGAAGGGGAAAAUGGCAGGAGGUGAGCUCAGCAAGGCAGAGGUGAGGAGAAGCUGUAGCUGGACUGAGGAACCAGAUCACCUGGGGCUUUAUUAGCUGUGAAAAGGAUGUGAGUUUUCAUUCUGAGUGAGAAUCUGAGUAGAGGAGAGACAUGAAGGGUUUUGGGGUUAGGAGGAUCCUUCUAGGCAUUGCCCCAUGAAGCAAGGGAAGAGGCUCAUGGUCUGAGGGCUGGGAAGAGUUAGAAACUGUAGCAAUAGACAAAAUGAGAGAUGGUGAGAGCUUGGGCCAGGAUAAUUGUAGUUGUGGUGGUGUGAGAUGGUUCAACUCAGGAUUUAUGUUAAAGAACCUAUCCAGUGAGUUUGCUCAACGAUUGGAUGUAAGGUAUGAUGAGAAAAAAAAAGGUUUGGGGCCUGAACAACUAGUGCAAGAGAGUUGUAUUUCACGAGGUGAGUAAGAACGUGGUGGGAUCAGGGGAUUUGGGUAGGUUAAUACCCAAAGGUAGGUAGAGGAAGGAAGAACUUGAUUUUAGACCUGCUAUGUUUGAAGGACAUGUUAGACACCAAUGGAGAUGUCAAGUAGACACUUGGAUUUAUGAGUUUAGAGUAAGAGAUGAAUUUUGGGCUAAAGAUAAAAAUUUACUAAGACAUAAUUUAAGUAGAAAAACUUACAUACCUUGAUGAGUGCUAGAUAAAAAUAUCUAAGAUCAUCCAAUACAGAUCAUUUUUAUGGAAAUGGAGAACCUAAAGCUCAGAAAAGUAGAAUGAGGUGCCCAAGGACACAGGUUUUUGGCAGAAUUCGUGUCAUUUGAUUCCUUGUCUUCUACUAUUUCCAGUCCAGCACGCAGUGUUUUAUUCAUGCUGAUAUAGUUCAGAAAUGGGGGGAACCUUACUAGUACAAAAGCCAGGAUAGUAAGCAAUGGUAUAAGGCAGGGUUUAAGAGCACAGACUCUGGAACAAACUUCCUAGGUUUAUUCCUCAUUCUCCCACAUACCUACUGUAUGACCUUGGUUAAAUUAUAUAGCUUCUCUGUGCUUCAGUUUCCUUAUCUGCAAACUGCAAUUGAUAAUAAUAGUAUGUACCUCACAGAGUACUUGGGAACUUAAUUGACAGGACAUAAGUAAAGCAUUUAAGUCACUAUGUUAAGUGCUAUCCAAGAGAAGCUGCAGCUAUGAUUUAUUAUUGUUAUUAAUAAUUAUUAUUCUAAGUCACUCAUUGGGAAAUCUUCAGAAAGUCUUUUCUUUAAACUUAGUUUUCCUACCUCAGAUGCAAAAUAAUAAAGUCUUCCAAUUGCUUCCUCUUUAAGAUUCUUAUUUCAGAGUGGAAGCCAUGAGCUUUCAUUACAACUUCUUGGGACCCAGAAUUAGCUUAUCUAGGGGGUAUUUAGAUACUAUGGAGAAGUCAUAUUGAGGUCAAAUAUUCUCAAAUCCCCUCUAUCCAGGGUUGCCUGUUCAUUCCCUGACAUUCGCAUCUACUGGUGCUUGUAAUUGGUUGGUAGCAUGCUCUGCUCUAUUGGAACAGUGUGUUCUUUUAAUUGAUUGCUUUCUGUGAGAAUGGCUUAUCUGCCUUUUUCAUUAACAUUCAUGAUUCUGUGACACUUCAUUCUCUCCAUUAAUAGCUUUAUGGAUGUCUUUUUAAUAGAGAUUUAAUCUUGCCUUUAACAUUUUAGGCAAUGUCUUGGUUAUCUACACUGUAACAUCUCAUUGUUGUGUGUUUAUGUUAUUAAUUCAUCAUUGUGUACUAAUCAAAACAAGUAAGCUCCUGUUUUUAACACCCCAUUCUUUGUGGAUAACAGUUGAUUUGUGGCAGGUUCUAGAUGAAUUGAAUAUUAUAAUUUAUGAGUAACAUUGGUUAAUUUUCUAGAGAGAAUAAUGAGAUUAUUGAUUAAGUUUUUUUUUUUUAUAAAGGAGAUUUAGUAACAGUGUCAGUGAAGAAGUGUGAAAGUCUCUCUUUAUUUCACUGGUUAGUGUGUGAUUAUUUUCCUUUCUCUGCCUGUCUUAGUUCAUUGUCUGUUGCUAUAACAGAAUACCUGAGACUGGAUAAUUUAUAAAAGAAAGAAGUUUAUUUAGCUUGCAAUUCUGGAGGCUGGGAAGUCCAAGAUGGAGUGGCCACAUCAGGUGAGGGCCUCAUGCUGCGUUAUAACAUGAUGGAAAACACCACAUGGUGGGAGAACUUGCGGGCGGGGCGGUGCAAAAGAAACAAGCACGAGAGGCUGAGCUUGCUUUGUAACAACCCGCUUUCAUGGUAACUAACUUACUCCCAUGAGAUUAACACACUCUCAUGAGAAAGACAUAAAUAACUCUUCAUGAUCAAAUUACCCCUUGAAGGCCCCACCACCUCCCAACCGUGCCAUGAUGGCAAUCACAUUUCAACAUGAGUUUCAGAGGAGACAAACCAUAUUCAAACCAUAGCACUGCCCGACAUGCUAAGUGUCAACCUUGAAGUAAAUCAAGUGUGUUAACAGAAGCAAGUUAUCCCAAGAUGAUUGGUCAUGCAGAUGGUAAGCAGUUGGACAGCAAAGAUUUAAUUUUGUAUCGAUUAUGCAUAUCAACUAAAUACCAUUUUUUUCCCGACUUAUUUGCUCUGUUUUUUUGUCAUUCGUGGUGGCAUUCAUGGAACUUCUACUCAGCAUGUGUUAGUCUUCUAGCCUCUCCUCAGACUUUUAUUAACCUUUGCUGUCUUGGAUGUGAAUUUUGUUCAAUAUUGUUUGGUAGGUUCUUGAUCCUUCCUCAAUGUCUGCAAGACACUCAGAAUAUCCUCGUUCACACUUUCAAGAUGAUCUUCCUAUCCUUAGGCAGAUAAGACAUGAGCUUGGAGCACAAUGUCUUCGUCUCCUGGUCACUGAUUCCUCUGGACUACAAUGAUGUCUGUUCUAUUAUUGCCAGUUUCCGAGGAACCGUUCCAUAUGGCCUGUCAUUGGAAAUUGGAGAUACAGUUCAGAUCCUGGAGAAGUGUGAUGGCUGGUACAGAGGAUUUGCCUUAAAAAACCCAAAUAUCAAGGGUAUAUUUCCUUCCAGCUACGUUCACUUGAAAAAUGCCUGUGUAAAGAACAAAGGACAAUUUGAAAUGGUUAUUCCCACUGAAGACUCUGUUAUCACAGAAAUGACAUCAACAUUAAGAGACUGGGGAACCAUGUGGAAACAACUCUAUGUGCGUAAUGAAGGCGAUCUCUUCCACCGGCUGUGGCACAUCAUGAAUGAAAUCCUGGACCUGAGGCGGCAGGUGCUGGUGGGCCACCUCACCCACGACCGGAUGAAGGACGUGAAGCGCCACAUUACUGCCCGGCUUGACUGGGGCAAUGAACAACUGGGACUGGACCUGGUGCCUAGGAAAGAGUACGCAAUGGUGGAUCCGGAAGACAUCAGCAUUACUGAGCUCUACCGAUUGAUGGAACAUCGACAUCGGAAGAAAGACACCCCGGUGCAGGCCAGCAGUCACCACCUCUUUGUCCAGAUGAAGAGCCUCAUGUGUUCCAACCUGGGAGAGGAGCUGGAGGUCAUCUUCUCACUCUUUGACAGUAAAGAGAACCGGCCAAUCAGUGAGAGAUUUUUCUUGAGGCUGAAUAGAAACGGGCUUCCCAAAGCCCCUGAUAAACCGGAACGACAUUGCUCCCUCUUUGUGGAUUUGGGCAGCAGUGAGCUAAGAAAGGACAUUUAUAUCACCGUGCACAUUAUCCGAAUCGGUCGAAUGGGAGCAGGAGAAAAAAAGAAUGCCUGUAGUGUCCAGUACCGACGACCCUUUGGCUGUGCAGUUCUUAGCAUCGCUGACCUGCUAACAGGAGAGACAAAGGAUGACCUCAUUCUGAAAGUAUACAUGUGUAACACAGAGAGUGAGUGGUACCAAAUCCAUGAGAACAUCAUCAAAAAGCUGAAUGCACGUUAUAACUUGACUGGCUCCAAUGCAGGUUUAGCAGUUUCCUUACAGCUAUUGCACGGAGACAUUGAACAAAUCAGAAGGGAAUAUUCAUCAGUAUUUUCUCAUGGAGUAUCCAUAACAAGGAAGCUGGGAUUUUCAAAUAUUAUUAUGCCUGGUGAAAUGAGGAAUGAUUUAUAUAUCACUAUUGAAAGGGGAGAAUUUGAGAAAGGAGGGAAGAGCGUGGCCAGAAAUGUGGAAGUUACGAUGUUCAUUGUAGACAGUAGUGGCCAAACCCUGAAGGAUUUUAUCUCCUUCGGCUCUGGGGAGCCACCAGCCAGUGAGUACCACUCCUUUGUGCUUUACCAUAACAACAGUCCCAGGUGGUCUGAACUGCUGAAACUUCCCAUUCCUGUGGAUAAAUUCCGGGGUGCACACAUCCGCUUCGAGUUUCGGCAUUGUUCCACAAAGGAGAAAGGAGAGAAGAAGUUGUUUGGGUUUUCUUUUGUCCCUCUGAUGCAAGAAGAUGGUAGGACUCUUCCAGAUGGCACUCAUGAGCUCAUCGUGCAUAAGUGUGAAGAAAACACAAAUCUUCAGGAUACUACCCGCUACCUCAAACUUCCCUUUUCCAAGGGCAUUUUCCUUGGGAAUAAUAAUCAAGCCAUGAAGGCCACAAAGGAGUCCUUUUGUAUUACAUCUUUUCUCUGUUCCACAAAACUCACACAAAAUGGUGAUAUGCUUGAUCUUUUGAAAUGGAGAACCCACCCAGACAAGAUCACUGGCUGUCUCUCUAAAUUAAAAGAAAUUGAUGGCUCAGAGAUAGUAAAGUUUCUGCAGGAUACACUGGAUACCUUAUUUGGAAUUUUAGAUGAAAAUUCCCAAAAAUAUGGGUCUAAAGUGUUUGAUUCUUUGGUUCACAUAAUAAAUUUGCUGCAAGAUAGCAAAUUUCAUCAUUUUAAACCUGUAAUGGACACUUACAUUGAGAGUCAUUUUGCUGGGGCACUUGCAUACAGAGAUCUCAUCAAAGUGCUCAAAUGGUACGUGGACCGGAUCACAGAAGCAGAGCGGCAAGAGCAUAUCCAGGAGGUGCUGAAGGCACAAGAAUACAUUUUUAAGUAUAUAGUUCAAUCUCGAAGGCUGUUUUCCCUUGCCACUGGUGGGCAAAACGAAGAGGAGUUCCGCUGCUGCAUUCAGGAGCUUCUCAUGUCAGUCCGUUUCUUUCUUUCGCAAGAGAGCAAAGGGUCUGGAGCAUUAUCUCAGUCACAGGCUGUGUUUCUGAGCUCUUUCCCUGCCGUGUACUCAGAACUGUUGAAGCUCUUUGAUGUCCGGGAAGUAGCCAACUUGGUCCAGGACACCCUGGGCAGUCUGCCGACCAUCCUGCAUGUGGAUGAUUCCCUGCAGGCCAUCAAACUGCAGUGCAUUGGCAAAACCGUGGAAAGCCAGCUUUAUACCAACCCAGAUUCCCGAUACAUUCUUCUGCCUGUCGUGUUACAUCACCUCCACAUUCACUUGCAAGAACAGAAGGACCUGAUCAUGUGUGCACGUAUCCUUAGCAACGUAUUUUGUCUUAUCAAGAAAAAUAGCUCAGAAAAAUCUGUGCUGGAGGAAAUAGAUGUGAUAGUGGCCAGCUUGCUGGAUAUUCUGCUGAGGACCAUAUUGGAGAUCACCAGCCGACCUCAGCCAUCCAGCUCAGCAAUGCGGUUCCAGUUCCAGGAUGUCACUGGGGAGUUUGUUGCUUGUCUCCUGUCCCUAUUACGACAAAUGACAGAUAGACAUUAUCAACAGCUUCUUGAUAGUUUUAAUACAAAGGAAGAACUAAGGGAUUUCCUGCUGCAGAUAUUUACUGUGUUCCGAAUAUUGAUACGCCCGGAGAUGUUUCCAAAGGACUGGACUGUUAUGCGCUUGGUUGCUAACAAUGUUAUUAUUACAACAGUUCUAUACCUCUCAGAUGCACUUCGUAAGAACUUCUUAAAUGAAAACUUUGAUUAUAAGAUCUGGGAUUCCUACUUUUACCUCGCAGUCAUUUUUAUAAACCAGUUGUGUCUGCAGUUGGAGAUGUUCACACCUUCCAAGAAGAAAAAGGUGUUAGAAAAGUAUGGUGACAUGCGGGUAACAAUGGGUUGUGAAAUUUUCAGCAUGUGGCAAAACCUAGGAGAGCACAAGCUUCAUUUUAUCCCUGCCCUGAUUGGCCCCUUCCUAGAAGUGACCUUGAUACCCCAGCCAGAUCUUCGGAAUGUCAUGAUUCCAAUUUUUCAUGAUAUGAUGGACUGGGAGCAGAGGCGGAGUGGCAACUUUAAACAGGUGGAAGCCAAGCUAAUUGACAAACUGGAUAGCCUGAUGUCAGAAGGCAAAGGUGACGAAACAUACCGCGAGCUCUUCAACAGUAUAAUUCCACUAUUUGGUCCCUAUCCUAGUCUACUAAAGAAAAUUGAGCGGGAAACAUGGCGGGAAAGUGGCGUUUCAUUAAUUGCUACUGUAACUCGUCUAAUGGAGAGGUUGUUAGAUUACAGGGACUGCAUGAAAAUGGGAGAGGUAGAUGGCAAAAAGAUUGGCUGCACAGUUAGCCUUCUGAACUUCUAUAAGACUGAACUGAACAAGGAGGAGAUGUAUAUACGCUACAUUCACAAACUCUAUGAUCUGCAUCUCAAAGCACAGAACUUUACAGAAGCUGCAUAUACCCUCCUCUUAUAUGACGAGCUACUGGAAUGGUCUGAUCGGCCCCUCAGGGAGUUCCUGACCUACCCCAUGCAAACAGAAUGGCAGCGCAAAGAGCACCUGCACCUCACCAUCAUCCAGAACUUUGACAGAGGCAAAUGUUGGGAGAAUGGCAUUAUCUUGUGCCGGAAGAUUGCAGAGCAGUAUGAGAGUUAUUAUGACUACAGAAACCUGAGCAAGAUGCGGAUGAUGGAAGCCUCUUUGUAUGACAAAAUUAUGGACCAGCAACGUCUUGAACCAGAGUUCUUCAGAGUUGGAUUUUAUGGAAAAAAAUUUCCAUUUUUCUUAAGAAAUAAGGAGUUUGUGUGUCGAGGGCAUGACUACGAGAGGCUGGAAGCCUUCCAACAGAGAAUGCUGAACGAGUUCCCCCAUGCCAUCGCCAUGCAGCACGCCAACCAGCCCGAUGAGACCAUCUUCCAGGCAGAAGCUCAGUAUUUGCAGAUAUAUGCUGUGACUCCCAUUCCAGAGAGCCAGGAGGUCCUGCAGAGAGAGGGUGUUCCGGACAACAUCAAAAGCUUCUAUAAAGUGAAUCACAUCUGGAAAUUCCGCUAUGACCGACCAUUUCACAAAGGCACAAAAGAUAAAGAGAAUGAAUUCAAGAGUCUCUGGGUGGAGAGAACGUCAUUAUACUUGGUGCAGAGUUUGCCUGGCAUCUCUCGCUGGUUUGAAGUGGAAAAGCGUGAAGUGGUAGAAAUGAGUCCUCUGGAAAAUGCAAUUGAAGUGCUAGAAAAUAAGAAUCAGCAGCUGAAGACUCUGAUUAGUCAGUGUCAGACAAGACAGAUGCAGAAUAUUAAUCCCCUGACUAUGUGCCUGAAUGGAGUUAUAGAUGCUGCAGUUAAUGGUGGCGUUUCCAGGUAUCAAGAGGCAUUCUUUGUCAAAGAAUAUAUCUUAAGUCACCCUGAAGAUGGGGAGAAAAUUGCACGAUUAAGAGAGCUGAUGCUUGAGCAGGCACAGAUUCUGGAAUUUGGUUUGGCCGUGCAUGAGAAGUUUGUACCUCAAGAUAUGAGACCCCUUCACAAAAAGCUGGUUGACCAAUUCUUUGUGAUGAAGUCGAGCUUAGGGAUACAGGAGUUCUCUGCUUGUAUGCAAGCCAGUCCUGUCCAUUUUCCUAAUGGAAGCCCUCGUGUGUGUAGAAACUCAGCACCUGCUUCUGUGAGCCCAGAUGGUACCAGGGUAAUUCCUAGACGCAGCCCGUUAAGUUACCCAGCUGUCAACCGAUAUUCUUCCUCCUCACUGUCCUCACAAGCUUCUGCUGAAGUAAGCAAUAUUACAGGGCAAUCAGAAAGCUCUGAUGAAGUCUUUAACAUGCAGCCAAGUCCAUCUACCUCAAGCUUGAGUUCUACUCACUCGGCUUCACCUAAUGUGACAAGUUCUGCUCCAUCGAGUGCCAGAGCUUCUCCUUUGUUGUCUGACAAACACAAACAUUCCCGAGAAAACUCUUGCCUGUCACCAAGAGAGAGACCAUGCAGUGCCAUCUAUCCAACACCUGUGGAGCCUUCGCAGAGGAUGCUGUUUAAUCAUAUUGGAGACGGGGCCUUGCCACGCAGUGACCCAAAUCUCUCUGCACCUGAAAAAGCUGUGAACCCCACCCCUAGCAGCUGGAGCCUGGACAGUGGGAAGGAAGCCAAGAACAUGUCGGAUAGUGGGAAACUUAUCUCUCCCCCUGUCCCUCCAAGACCCACACAGACUGCUUCACCAGCAAGACACACGACAUCAGUAUCCCCCUCGCCUGCCGGGCGAUCUCCAUUGAAGGGCUCUGUGCAGUCUUUCACCCCCUCUCCAGUGGAGUACCACUCGCCAGGACUCAUCUCCAACUCCCCUGUCUUGUCGGGCAGCUACAGCAGUGGGAUUUCUUCUCUCAGCCGGUGCAGCACGUCGGAAACCUCAGGCUUUGAAAAUCAGGUGAAUGAACAGUCGGCCCCCCUGCCGGUGCCAGUGCCGGUGCCCGUGCCGAGCUACGGCGGGGAGGAGCCAGUGCGCAAGGAGAGCAAGACUCCGCCCCCGUACAGCGUCUACGAGCGGACUCUGCGGCGCCCCGUCCCGCUACCUCACAGCCUCUCCAUCCCCGUCACGUCGGAGCCGCCCGCGCUGCCCCCCAAGCCUCUGGCAGCGCGAUCCAGCCACCUGGAGAAUGGGGCCCGGAGGACUGACCCCGGCCCGCGGCCCAGGCCCCUGCCCCGCAAGGUCUCUCAGUUAUAAGUCACUUUUCUAUGUACCUGCGAUGCAUUCUUUGCCCGUUUACAAAAUAAGAAGUAUGAUGAGAAGACAUUUAGUGUAGGCACUUUAAUAACUUACUCAGCUCCUUCGAUGAAUGGAAUUAAAACUUGCUUAUUAAAUAUCAUGUUGCACAAUAUUAAAAGUUGCUGAUCUAAAACGCCAGAUGUUAAAUGAAGUAUGGCUGAAUUUCAUUAAAACGUUUCUCAUUUGGAAGUGGUAAAUAGUGAUAAAGACUCCUUUUGUACCUUUUUAUGUUCACUUUUUUUUAUAUAGUUUAAUCUUAAAACCAAUACGAUAUUGUCAAACGAUACAAUGUGUGACAAUGUUGUAUCGUUUUUACUGAAUACUUGAUACUUGGAGAAAGCUUAUUAAGUCAGUGCACAUCCUAACACAGUGGUCCUUAUUUUAGAAGACUUCUGUAAAUAAGGCAAGGUUUAUCAGUGCAGAUCAUCAGAAUUAAAGUUCAAGCAGGCGAGCAAGACAGUAUACUUAAGGGGUUGCAAAGCUUGGGACUGGAAAUUGUUUUGUUCUUGAAACAAAAUACUUCUUUAAGGUUGCUUUUGCUGUUUGACUGCUGUCUACAUUCGUAAAAUUCUAUUUUGUGAAUUGGUAGCUAAAUCCCUUACUACCCUGACACCGUGGUAUCUACUGUAUUUCUUUUCAAGGUGCAAUUUGCUUCAGAGUUCCAAUCAGCUAGAUUAAGCAAGAGGCUCCAGAAGAAAUGUUUACUUGAAUUUUGCGCUUCCUUUCUUGAUAGUUUCCUAUAUAAAAUUUGUCAUUGAACAAGAGCAAAUGCUGAAGUAUUAAUGAGGCACAAAUGACUGUGCCCCAUUAGCAAGAAUUCAGGAAUCAAUACAGACAGUAUUAAAUUAAUAGCUUAAGUGAAGAAAAAAAAAACUUAGUGAAAAUGUAUUAGCACGAUUAAAUGGCAAAAGGACUUAUAAAAGGCAAGGGCAUUAACUUUCAGUCCUGCACAAAAUAAAAAAUUCCUCACGACUCUCCACUUUUACCAGUGGAGUUUGUCUUAGCUGACCUGUCGUCUUUCUCUUGAAGGAGGAUUGCUGUAGACUUCUCUAGCUUGAAUAUUGCAACAUAGCAUCUUAGGUCUAGAUAGGGAUGCUAAUGCCAGUUGUAGAAGUGUGAAAAAAGCACCUUGUAUGUAGUAAUGUAUUUUAUAUCUUUGUUUUUUCUUUUACUGACUGUUUAUAACACUCAAUUGACAAUAGAUAUGAACUGUAUUUUAAAUCAUACUGUUAAAUAUUUUCCCUCUUUUGUUGGGAAGCUCAUUUUAGUUUAACCAUGUUUGUUUUGUUGGUAGCUUACCUGGAAGGCAGUGACCACUUUUUUAUAUUCUCUUAAUGAAACCAUUCAGCAGGUAUAUGCUGUUGAGGCUGGUUAUAGAGGUUUUCUAUAAUAAAUGUUCAAGUAUUUUUGUAUAUAACUGGUUAAUUUUAAUAAGAGAUACCAUUAUGUGUAAAAAAAAGUAAAAAUAAACGCAAACAGUUGUUGAUGCAGUAUGAUUGUUAUAAUUAUGCCAAAUACUUUACGUAUGGAAAAAGAAUAUUUGUACAUAUGUGCUUUUAACAAUUCUGCCAUAUUGACUUUACAAUUUUGAAUGUCGGAAAAAUUAAUAUAUGUUAAAUAUUUAUGUUUAGUGAAAGUGUUCAUAAUUGAGAAAAGGAACAUAUGCAUUUUAGCUUUGUAUCUUGCAAGUUUUGCAGUCAGAAAUUUUUUGAACUAGCUUUUGCUUUUGAUAACACUUCGUGUUUGUAACCACAUUCAUAUAUAUAUACAUAUAUAUGUGAAGCUCCAUAUUUCUGUUGCUUUAAAGAAGUAAAACCUUCCAUUUAAAUAAGAUGACAUGCAUAAGAUAACAAAGCUUCCUUGAUUUCCUUUUCCUGUGUAAUUUAAUAGAUUUGUUGACUAGUGCUUGGGCACAUUAUAAAUCAGUGUUAUUUGCUCUUGGAGCCAUUUUUUAAAAAAAAUUUUGGCAGUGAGCAGUUGAAUUUAUCUUGAAUUUAUCAUGUGUGUGUAUUUCUGAAGCAGCUACAUAGCAGAACAUUUUAAGAGAUUCUGUUAGCCCACAUGUUCAUGUUGGUUGCUGCUGAAUGGUAAAUAUUAAAUAAAAUUACCAGAUUAAUCUUAA